AGGAUUAUAGGUUUUUAGGUCACGCAGAAACCCUGGGGAACGCCUGAAAAGGCUAAACACAAGCAGUUACAUUAUGCACAAGCUGGAUGACGUGACCCCGCUGCUGCUGUGUGGAGAGGGAGGCUGCUGAACCCGAGCUGGUGUGAGCUUCUCUUGCCGUAAGUCCACGGGUGGCCAGGAGCACGUGUUAGUCUGGUUAAGAGCUCUGCUCAGAAGUAGCCGCUGCAGCUGAAGGUUUUCAGGCGGGCUGAAGGCUGGGCCGCUUCUUCAUUCAUUUCAGAAACUUGAACAGUGGGCCUUCUACACACGCUGUCUUUGUCAGCCUCAGGCAGUUCCUCCAUGGAUGAGACACAGGGGCCUCUGGCCAUGACUGUCCAUCUUCUUGCCAACUCUGGGCACGGCUCCCUUCUGCAGAGGACUCUGGACCAGCUCCUGGAUUGCAUUUGCCCAGAGGUCCGGCUCUUUCAGGUGUCUGAACGGGCCAGUCCUGUGAAAUACUGUGAAAAGUCCCAUUCCAAGCGGUCCCGGUUUCCAGGGAUGUCCGUGUUGCUCUUCCUGCACGAAAGCCCGGGAGAGGAUAGGCUAUUUCGCGUCCUGGACUCUCUCCAGCAUUCGCCAUGGCAGUGCUACCCCACCCAGGACACUCGGGGAAGGCUGUGUCCCUACUUUUUUGCCAAUCAGGAGUUCUACAGCCUGGACAGUCAGCUGCCCAUCUGGGGGGUGAGGCAGGUGCACUGUGGCUCCGAGAUCCUGAGGGUGACGCUGUACUGCAGUUUUGAUAACUAUGAAGACGCCAUCAGACUCUACGAGAUGAUCCUGCAGAGAGAAGCGACCUUGCAAAAGAGCAAUUUUUGUUUCUUCGUGCUCUAUGCCUCCAAGAGCUUUGCUCUGCAGCUCUCCCUGAAGCAGCUGCCCCCGGGAAUGUCAGUGGACCCCAAAGAGUCUUCGGUGCUGCAGUUUAAGGUUCAAGAGAUCGGCCAGUUAGUGCCUCUGCUACCCAAUCCAUGCAUGCCUAUCAGCAGCACCAGGUGGCAGACUCAGGACUACGAUGGCAACAAGAUUCUGCUUCAGAGAUGGGAGUCUUCCUCUGUUGCCCAGACUCGAGUGCGGUGGUGCCAUCAUAGCUCCCUGAGGUCUUCACCUUCUGGGUUCAAGUGAUCCUCCUGCCUUAGCCUCCUGAUUAGCUGGGACUACAGGUUCAGCUGAAUCCAGAACUUGGUGUUAAGAAUGGCAUCUUGGGAGCUGGCAUGCUUCCCCUGGGCUCCAGGCUGACUUCUGUCUCUGCAAAGAGGACCUCAGAACCCAGGAGCCAGAGGAACCAGGGCAAGAGGUCCCAGGGGCAUUCUCUGGAGCUUCCUGAGCCCAGUGGGAGCCCCACAUCAGACAGGUGUGCUGGCACUUCGUGGAAAAGCCCUGGCCGGUCAUUCCAGGUCAGCAGCCCAGCUAUGGGUGCCCACCUGCACCUGUCUUCUCAUCACCUUGAAUCCGGGGCCAGAAUGAAGGUCCUCAACCGGGAAAACAGCUUUCAGAAGCUUGAGGCCGAGACGAAUGUUGACACCGGCUUGACCAUCAUAAAUUCUGAACCCAGGCAGACUUAUUUUGGCGGAUUUCCAAGGGAUUUACAGACCAGCCAGCCACCAUUCUGCUUGCCAGCCUCUUCCUUGGGGGUGGCUACCUCCAAAAACAACAGUGUCCUUAAGGAAAGAGUCUCUCCUUUGCCACUUGCUGGCCAAAGGGACCUUGGUACCAGGAAGACAAUUUCAGAAUGUCUCCUUCAUCUGCAAGUUCAGGGUGAAGAAAAAGAAGAAGAUGAAGAAGAAUUCUUUAUAUAGCAUAAAAUAAAUGUGGUUUUCUAAAACACAAGAUCAGAUAAAAUGUUCUAGAAAUGGAGUACUGACCCAGAAUCAGCCUGUUAGUUGUUCAUCUGAGGGGGGCUGAAUGCUCCCCAUGCACAAUCUGUAUUGAUUUUAUUUCAAAUGUUCAAAGUCUAAAGGUGCUGGGAAUGAUUGUUUAUUUGCCGUCACAGUCAUAAGAGAACACAGCCAACACACAGGGAAAAAAACCGAAUGCUUUUGUUCCGUGGAGAUGCACUAACCCAGCUGGAUGUGUUGAAUCCAGCACCUAUCAGGAUAAUUGCAUUGUAUGCAAAUGAAUCGGUAUGUUAUACAACACUAAUUAGUGUCUGUAAUUUGGUUUUAAUUUUUACUUAGGUUGCAUAGCUCAUCCCCCUGGACAAUAUGGACUGCUAUUUACUCUUGAAUGCUUUUUAAUUUUCAUGUGACCUCUUUUGGUAACUAGGCCUUGUUCACAUACCCUCCUUGUGAUUUUGUCUUUAAAGUUGUUUGUAUCUGGAAUGAGUGAAAAUGCAAAGUGUUUUGAAAAUUAUAAACAGUUAAUUUUGUUUUCCUGUUUAAUGAGCCAAAAUACUGGAAGCCAGAAAAUCAGGUUGAACAUGAAUGCUAGGCUCUAGGGCUUUCCUGCUCAUCUGCUUCUCAUUUGUUUCUGCACUAUGUCAAAGAGGACAGUGGUUCUUGUUACAAACCAAAGAGGAACAUUGAGCACAGUGGGAAAAUUGGACUGGUUGAUCUGGUCACUGGAGCAGGACUUGGGUUCUUCUGGCCAGAUUUUGACUCCCAGAUUCCUUUACAAAACGCACUCAUUCAUUCAUUUAUAUAUGUUCAUUCAAUAAACAUUUUUUGAAUACCUA